AGGCUUCUGAGAAGACUGGUGGGAGAGAAGGAGAGCCUGCAGACAGAGGCCUCCAGCUUGGUCUGUCUCCCCACCUCUACCAGCAUCUGCUGAGCUAUGAGCCAAACCAGGGAUUUACAGGGAGGAAAAGCUUUCGGACUGCUGAAGGCCCAGCAGGAAGAGAGGCUGGAUGAGAUCAACAAGCAAUUCCUAGACGAUCCCAAAUAUAGCAGUGAUGAGGAUCUGCCCUCCAAACUGGAAGGCUUCAAAGAGAAAUACAUGGAGUUUGACCUUAAUGGAAAUGGCGAUAUUGGUGAGAAACGGGUGAUUUGCGGGGGCAGGGUGGUGUGCAGGCCUAAGAAGACAGAGGUCUCUCCUACAUGCUCCAUUCCUCAUGAUUUGGGAGGGGGCCCACCUACCACAGUGGGAGGAAGGAGAAUGGGGAUGCGGAAGUGGGAGAGGAGAGAGAGGGUCUCCCCACCUUCUCCCCAUCCCCAUCCUCUGCCCCCAGAUAUCAUGUCCCUGAAACGAAUGCUGGAGAAACUUGGAGUCCCCAAGACUCACCUAGAGCUAAAGAAAUUAAUUGGAGAGGUGUCCAGUGGCUCCGGGGAGACGUUCAGCUACCCUGACUUUCUCAGGAUGAUGCUGGGCAAGAGAUCUGCCAUCCUAAAAAUGUGA